GUCUGAGGGUCGGACUCCACGUCAGGCUGUCUCUGGCCUGUCCCCUCAGUUCCCAGGUGCCAUGAGGAAGCCUCGUCGGAAGUCCCGGCAGAAUGCCGAGGGCCGGCGUUCCCCGUCCCCCUACAGUCUCAAGUGCUCACCCACCCGGGAGACCCUGACAUAUGCCCAGGCCCAGCGGAUUGUCGAGGUAGACAUUGAUGGACGCCUGCAUCGUAUCAGCAUCUAUGACCCACUCAAAAUCAUUACUGAAGAUGAGCUAACUGCCCAGGAUAUCACCGAAUGCAAUAGUAACAAGGAAAACAGUGAACAGCCUCAGUUCCCUGGCAAGUCCAAGAAACCCUCAUCCAAGGGCAAAAAGAAGGAAUCCUGCUCCAAGCAUGCAUCUGGUACUUCCUUCCACCUCCCACAGCCCAGCUUCCGUAUGGUGGACUCAGGCAUCCAGCCAGAAGCACCCCCGCUGCCUGCUGCCUACUACCGCUACAUUGAGAAGCCACCUGAAGACCUGGAUGCAGAGGUAGAGUAUGACAUGGAUGAGGAGGACCUUGCCUGGCUGGACAUGGUGAAUGAAAAACGGCGAGUAGAUGGGCACAGUUUGGUGUCUGCAGAUACCUUUGAGCUGCUGGUAGACCGGCUUGAGAAAGAGUCAUACUUGGAGAGUCGCAGCAGUGGGGCCCAACAGUCACUCAUCGAUGAAGACGCUUUCUGCUGUGUGUGCCUGGAUGAUGAAUGUCACAAUAGCAAUGUUAUUCUCUUCUGUGACAUCUGCAACCUGGCUGUACACCAGGAGUGCUAUGGCGUCCCAUACAUCCCUGAGGGCCAGUGGCUAUGCCGCUGCUGCCUGCAGUCUCCCUCCCGGCCUGUGGAUUGCAUCCUUUGCCCCAAUAAGGGUGGCGCCUUCAAACAGACCAGUGAUGGGCACUGGGCCCAUGUGGUGUGUGCCAUCUGGAUCCCUGAAGUCUGCUUUGCUAACACCGUGUUCUUGGAACCUAUUGAGGGCAUUGACAAUAUCCCGCCUGCCCGCUGGAAACUAACCUGCUAUAUCUGCAAGCAGAAAGGGCUAGGUGCAGCCAUCCAGUGCCAUAAGGUGAACUGCUACACAGCAUUCCAUGUGACAUGUGCACAGCGGGCUGGGCUCUUCAUGAAGAUUGAGCCCAUGCGCGAAACCAGCCUCAAUGGCACCAUCUUUACAGUGCGCAAGACUGCCUACUGUGAGGCCCACUCGCCACCAGGUGCGGCCACUGCUAGGAGGAAGGGCGACUCCCCUAGAAGCAUCAGUGAGACUGGCGAUGAGGAAGGGCUGAAGGAGGGUGAUGGAGAGGAGGAAGAAGAGGAAGAGGUGGAGGAAGAAGAGCAGGAAGCUCAAGGCGGGGUGAGUGGCUCCCUCAAGGGAGUGCCCAAGAAAAGCAAGAUGAGUUUGAAGCAGAAGAUCAAGAAGGAGCCAGAGGAAGCAGGCCAAGACACACCCUCCACUCUCCCCAUGCUUGCUGUCCCACAGAUACCCUCUUACAGGUUGAACAAGAUCUGUAGUGGUCUCUCCUUUCAGAGGAAAAACCAGUUUAUGCAGCGGCUUCACAAUUAUUGGCUGUUGAAGCGGCAGGCACGGAAUGGUGUCCCUCUUAUCCGGCGCUUGCACUCCCAUCUGCAGUCCCAAAGAAACGCUGAGCAGCGAGAGCAGGAUGAGAAGACAAGUGCAGUGAAGGAGGAGCUGAAGUAUUGGCAGAAGCUCCGGCAUGACUUGGAGCGGGCGCGGCUGCUGAUUGAGCUGAUUCGGAAGAGAGAGAAGCUCAAACGAGAGCAGGUCAAAGUCCAGCAGGCUGCCAUGGAGCUGGAGCUGAUGCCAUUCAAUGUUCUGUUGAGGACAACACUGGACCUGCUGCAGGAGAAGGAUCCUGCACACAUCUUCGCAGAACCAGUCAACUUGAGUGAGGUUCCAGAUUACCUGGAAUUCAUAUCCAAGCCAAUGGAUUUUUCUACUAUGAGGCGGAAGCUGGAGUCCCACCUGUACCGCACCUUGGAGGAGUUUGAGGAGGACUUUAACCUUAUAGUUACCAACUGCAUGAAGUAUAAUGCUAAAGACACAAUUUUCCACCGAGCAGCUGUCCGCCUGCGGGACCUGGGAGGGGCCAUCCUACGGCACGCCCGGCGGCAGGCAGAGAACAUCGGCUAUGACCCCGAGAGGGGCACUCACCUGCCCGAGUCACCCAAAUUGGAAGACUUUUACCGCUUCUCCUGGGAAGACGUGGACAACAUCCUCAUCCCAGAGAACCGGGCCCAUUUGUCCCCAGAGGUGCAGCUGAAGGAGCUGCUGGAGAAACUGGACCUGGUGAGCGCCAUGCGGUCCAGUGGGGCCCGCACCCGUCGUGUCCGCCUGCUACGCCGGGAGAUCAAUGCCCUUCGGCAGAAGCUGGCACAGCCACCACCACCACAGCCACCAUCACUCAACAAGACAGUAUCCAAUGGGGAGCUGCCAGCAGGGCCCCAGGGGGAUGCAGCUGUGCUGGAGCAGGCCUUGCAGGAGGAGCCAGAAGACGAUGGGGACAGAGAUGACUCCAAACUGCCUCCUCCGCCAACCCUGGAGCCCACUGGGCCUGCACCUUCCUUGUCUGAGCAAGAAUCCCCCCCGGAGCCCCCUACUCUGAAACCCAUUAAUGAUAGCAAACCUCCAAGCAGGUUCCUAAAGCCCAGAAAGGUGGAAGAAGAUGAGCUCUUGGAAAAAUCACCACUGCAGCUAGGGAAUGAGCCUUUGCAACGCUUGCUCAGUGACAAUGGCAUCAACAGACUAUCCCUCAUGGCCCCUGACACCCCGGCCGGUACCCCACUUAGUGGUGUGGGUCGCCGCACAUCAGUCCUCUUCAAGAAGGCCAAGAAUGGGGUUAAGCUACAGAGAAGCCCAGACAGGGUCCUGGAGAAUGGCGAGGACCAUGGUGUGGCAGGCUCUCCUGCCUCUCCAGCCAGCAUCGAGGAAGAGCGCCACUCCCGGAAGCGGCCAAGGAGCAGGAGCUGUAGUGAGAGCGAAGGGGAGAGGUCCCCCCAGCAGGAGGAAGAGACAGGCAUGACCAACGGCUUUGGAAAACACACCGAAAGCGGGUCUGACUCUGAAUGUAGUUUGGGUCUCAGUGGUGGACUGGCAUUUGAAGCUUGCAGUGGUCUGACGCCCCCCAAACGCAGCCGUGGGAAGCCAGCCCUGUCUCGAGUGCCCUUCCUGGAAGGUGUGAACGGAGACUCUGACUACAAUGGCUCAGGCAGAAGCCUCCUGCUGCCCUUUGAAGACCGCGGAGACCUGGAGCCCUUGGAGCUGGUGUGGGCCAAGUGCCGAGGCUACCCCUCCUACCCUGCCUUGAUCAUCGAUCCCAAGAUGCCCCGGGAGGGCCUCCUGCACAAUGGCGUUCCCAUCCCUGUCCCCCCGCUGGACGUGCUGAAGCUGGGAGAGCAGAAACAGGCAGAGGCUGGAGAGAAGCUCUUCCUUGUCCUCUUCUUUGACAACAAGCGCACCUGAUGAGGAAGUUGAGGCUCAGAAAGUCCAGACCCUGUAGCCAGAACUAAGAUACAAAACAAGAUCUUGCUCCAAAGGCUGUAUCCUUAGCCACAUGUUAUAUUCACCCGGGGAGCUUUAAAAACACAUACACAGUGUGCAGGUCCCACCACAGAUGAGUUUAUCAGUUCCUGGCAUCAGCUCUACUUCCUAGCCAUCGCCCCCUAAUUCUCCAACGCAAGGCGAGGCUCAGAGCCCUCCAGGGUGGCUCAGCUGGCCCCAGAGGGCAGCAGGUGGGCCUUUCUUAGCCUAUGGACCCUUACAACUCUCCAAACAGAGUAAGGGCCCAGAGAAGGACCUAGCUGCAAAAUUGAUUCCAUGCCAUUCCCCCACCCGACUCCUGCAUAUCCUGCUUGCUGUCCUCACCUGCUAGGUUCUUGGUGGCCUCCUGCAUGGAGUCCCCCAAUUUGCUUCCCUCUGCCCUGUACCCUCUCCCUGGCUUUGCUGGUCCUGGCCAAGUGGGGCCACAGGAGCCCGAGCCCCCUGUGAGACCCACUACUGCCCAGCCUCUUACUGUGCUUGCAUUUCAGGCAGUGGCUUCCAAGGGACAAAGUCCUGCCCUUGGGUGUGGAAGACACCGUGGACAAGCUCAAGAUGCUGGAAGGCCGCAAGACCAGCAUCCGCAAGUCAGUGCAGGUGGCCUAUGACCGUGCGAUGAUCCACCUGAGCAGAGUCCGGGGGCCCCACUCCUUCGUCACUUCCAGCUACCUGUAAGGGCAGGGCUGGGCCUGCAUCCGCUUGCCCUGCCUCCAUCCCGCAGGGCACAGAGAAGCCUCUUCUGCCCCUGCCAGAUGUAUGGCCGGCAGCUUCCCCCUCUCAUGGUAGGCCAGGGACUGGGCUUUCUCCCCACUAAGGGCAAGGCCCCAGUUUUGACCAAUCGCAUGGUUCUCCUGGCAGGCCUGCUGUGUGCCAAAAACUCCCACCCAAGGUCCCUCAGGGGAUAUUUCACUGAAGAACCAGUUAGAAGUAGAAACAGCUGUGGGGCUUGGGCCCAGCUUAGGAGAUUGCCCAGAUGGCAAGAGGUCCUGGGCUCCUUCUUGAGGGGCUGCCUGGCCCGCUCCAUCCUACUCCCACUAACUACACCUCAGGGCGGGUGAGGUUCCGACACUGAUCCCAGAGAUGCCGUGGAUACGCCAGGGUCCCAGGGGGAAUCUCCCCAAGCUCACACUCUCUCCCGCUUAUCGCCUAUUCUCACACCUCUUCUCGGUCCCAUCUUCUGCACCCAUUGCCCAGUCUUGCUUUCUCUUUCCCAUAUUCCUUUUCUUUUUCUCUUGUGCCAAACUGACAGAAACCGUCACCACACUGGUCUUUUUCUUUAAUGUCUCAUUCCCCUUGAGGCCAGCUGCUAUGCCAGGUGGUGUCUCUGCCAGGCUCCUCAGGCCCAGACAGAGGCCAGCCCACAACCUAUGACCCCCUCCCCCAGGACACCACCUCCCACCCACAGACCUUCCCUUUAGCUGUUGACACAACUUCCCAGCUCUGCAAGUGUGCCCCCUGGAUCAAGGCGGGUCCCCUCUUGUUUUUUUCUUUGCUGCCACGAGGUGGUCCAAGCCUUCAGGGUGGGCUCCUAUCAGGCUGGGUGUGCGAGUGUCCAUCUGUCCACAUGGAUGUCGAGGGUGGUUUGUGUGGAGCUGUGCUCGUCAGCUGGGUCUGCCCUCUUCCCCCUUUUCUCCUUCUUCUCUCCUCAUGGACUUUUUCUGCAAUUGCAGUCUUAAGCUUCACUCUCCACCACCUGGAUGGCAUGGCGCCUGCCACCAAACAUCUUCCUGGCCUGCGCUCUGCCCUGCCCUGCCUAGCCUCUGCUACUCCCACUUCCCAACUCCAGGGAAUGCAUUACUUUUAUUUCAAACCCUCUGCCUCCUUCCUUCUUUCUCUUCAACCCCCUCCCCACCUUCACCUUCUCAAAAAUGGAAGGAAAAAAAAACUGUGAAUGGGGAAUGCUGACUGACAAACCAACACAACUUUCAGAGGCUUCAGUGUCUGUUCUCUGGACAUUUCUUUUCACCUCCUGAGCACCAAAGUCGCAGGGCCAGUUGCAGGCCGCUGAUUGCCAUGUUGAUUUUUAACCUGAUAUUCUUUUUAAUUGUUUUAAAUUUUUCAUAGGGGAGUUUUGGACAAAACAGUCACUGGGGAGAUCACUGCCAUUUUUACACACUUGACUUUUUAAAAAUACAACCAACCAACCACCACAACUUCUUAUACAUUUGGGACAUGAGCCAGAGUUUAAAAGGGAACCAACAAAACACUAUAACUUAAAAGGAUGGGGUUUUGGAUUUUGUAUAAUAAUAAAAACAAUACAGCAUAUGGCUAGGGAAGGACAUGGUGUAUAUAAUUGUAAAAUACUGUUCUAAAUUAUUCAGGCCUAUAGUUUCCAUUACUGGAGUCCUCCAUUGUGUGGCCACACAGUGUCGUUGAUUUAAAGGAGCCAGUGCUUCCCCUCUCCCCAGGUAGUUGGUCAGCUGUGGACUCUGUGACCUUUGUCUAAACCUGUGUUGUAAGAUCUUGGGACUUCCUCUCUUUCUAUGUCUAUCUCUUCCCCCCAACACUUUCUCUUCUUAGUCUCUCUCUUUAUUUUUCAAUCUCUGAAUAUUUUAGUCUCUCUCUGAGUCUCAUUUUUUAAAAUGCUCUUUUAGAACGGGAAACGGCUCAGAUCCUGCUGUGGCACGGGGCCUAUGUGUCUCUGUCGCGUCUGCUGUGAAGCACAUGAUGCUCUAUUUAUUGUAGAGAGUGACUUUAUUUGCUUUCUAGAAUUGUUUAUAACAGAUGGUAUAAGAGAGGUAAUAAACAGAGAAAAAUCUAUGCUUGUAAAGAAUACAAAAGUUAAUUUUACCUACUAUAAUAUGACUGUCUGAAACUUAUUUUCUCUCUGAGAAAUAAAUGUUCUAAUGGGCAGUA